GUCCGGAGCUCGGCGGUGGCGCCGGAGGAGGCUGCAGCGGCGGCGGCGGCGGGCCCGGACGAGCGUCCGGAGGUGGCGGACGAGGCGCCGGGGGCCCCCAUGGGCGGGUGUGUGGGCGCCCAGCACGACUCCUCGGGCAGCCUCAACGAGAACUCGGAGGGCACCGGAGGUUAAUACAAAGGGUAAAGGAACAAGUUAAAAUGUCUUCACACAUUGCCGUAUAUCCCCUGGAGGGCAAAACUGUCCCCAGCUGAGAAAUGCUGGCCUACAUCAAAUGACAACACAUAAGCCUUGAUUGGAACUUGUUGCUCUAGGUCGUAACCAGCCUUUGAAAAAGGAGAAACCAAAAUGGAAAAGCGAUUAUCCUAUGACAGAUGGACAACUACGCAGCAAGAGGGAUGAAUUUUGGGAUACAGCACCAGCUUUUGAAGGCCGGAAAGAGAUUUGGGAUGCCUUGAAGGCUGCUGCACAUGCUUUUGAGAGCAAUGAUCAUGAACUGGCACAAGCAAUCAUUGAUGGUGCAAACAUAACAUUACCACAUGGUGCACUUACAGAGUGCUACGAUGAACUGGGGAACAGAUAUCAGCUUCCAGUGUAUUGCUUGGCACCGCCAAUCAACAUGAUAGAGGAAAAGAGCGACAUAGAGACUCUGGAUAUUCCUGAGCCACCACCCAAUUCUGGAUAUGAAUGUCAGCUUCGUUUGCGCCUUUCCACAGGCAAAGACCUCAAGCUUGUGGUUCGCAGCACAGACACAGUAUUCCACAUGAAGAGACGGUUGCAUGCAGCAGAGGGAGUGGAACCAGGUAGUCAGCGGUGGUUUUUUUCUGGCAGACCUCUCACUGACAAAAUGAAGUUCGAAGAGCUGAAGAUCCCAAAGGACUAUGUUGUACAGGUUAUAGUGAGCCAACCUGUGCAGAACCCAACACCAGUGGAGAACUGAACUGAGCCCUGUUGGCCAGCUCCCACAUCCCUCUGCUCCUUUUUAUGGUUCUUGUUGUCAUUUCCUACUCUGCGGCGUGAAAUCUAUUUCACUGCUCUAAAUUCCCUAUGAAUGGAUUUAGUUCUGAGGAAUUACCAGUGAAAAAUUCCAUCUGUGAUGGAGACCAACAAAAAUAAUAAAACACAAAGAGCCAGGCUUUGAGACUCAUGUAAUUACAAUUUCUAAUUUGAAAGGCAGUUAAGAAAUAGAUAACCAUUUAUUUUAGAACACUCAACAACUAUGUAAUGGCUAUAUUUCAGUGACUUGGACUGUAAAUGAAACAUUGCAUCCAUGAAGGACAGCACCAAGCACCUUUUUGAAUACAGAAUUUUUUUAGAAAAAUAUAUCAAAUUAUAUAAUUUCCAGAAACCAUAAAUAAUGGAUAUAAAACUUAACCUUUUUGUUUUGUUUUGUUUUGUUUUGUUUUGUUUUGUUUUGUUUUGGUUAAUGGAAACUGAAAAGAGCAGUAUUUGAGGUUGCUUCUAUUCUGGUUUUUUAUUCUUAGCUCAAUUAAUAUUUAGCCAUAAAUGAGUAGAGACUGGCAAAUUGUGCUUUAGUGUUGCUUUCCUCAUCCCCACAUCUUGAGCUCCUUAUUUACAUUCACACUAAAUUUUGGUGCCUUCCAGCACAUUAGUGGCAGGCACCCUUCUGGAACACUAGGCAAUAAUUUCAUCAAUACAGUCAGGUCUCUUGAGUUUCAACAGAUACUCAGUUGAAAAGUCGCUGUCAUCUUGCUGCAUAAGUAUUUUGAAAGGUCUGUAUAACGAAGCCAUUUUUAUAUCCAGGCUUAGAAGGUCACUACUAUAUAGUACCUUCAUUGAUCUAUCUAUUCUGCUUGGAACUUUUCAUAGCUAAGUAUAACCCCCAAAUGCAUGGUUCCUGGGUCAGGAGACACCAAAAUCAAUUAUAGCUGUUCCCACUCAAGUUAAUAAAGUAAAUGAUUUCCUCCACUUUGCAUGGAGGGGUGUAAGGAAAGCCUAUUUUAUCUGUGCCUGGGAGAACUGUGCCUAUUUUCAGUCUUUUAGAGGAAAUUUCAACUCAAAAUUUUUAAGUGUGAAAGAUUUACUGGUGUCACAUAAACAUUAGCAGUGAGACCAAAUAAUGAAACAUUGCUUUAUACCUUAGUGCUUUCCAGUUCACUGUUACCUCUAGUCAUGGUAGAUGACAAUUUUCCUCCCUCAUCUUUUGUAGCAAAGAAGCAAAUUAAGAGCCUUUUGCAAGUUAGAUUAGGGGACUGAAAAAUCCAGGGAGAUAACCUGAUUCUUCUAUACUAUGACUGGAGUAAAGCUGCCAAGAGUUAGGUUGAAUUUGGAGCCUUUUAAAAGUUGGUUCCAUAAGUGAGAAGGGGGGCUAACAUGUGACCACUGUGCCCCUGAGAAUCCAUGAGAUGGAAAAGUACAGACAAGAAGGCACUUAACGCUGUUCUCAGUUGGAAAAUGUCAGCCCUCCACACCUGUUUGGAUGUGAAGUGCAUUAUUAAUUUUAAUGACAAAAUGAAACUGCUAAUUAGUUUAAAUGUAAUGUUUAAAUGGUAUUGAAUUUCCUAUUGCCUGAUUAAAUAUAUCUGUAAUUGUAACAUCAUGUUUCUGAGAGCUUUAACUACUUCCUUAUUUUUAUGCAAUCAUUUUAAAGAUUGUGGCUAUAUCUAAUUUAAAUUUGCUGAUGAUUGAAUCUAAAUUCAAGUGAAGACCACAGCAUUAAUCCCAAAGGAGAUUUUUUUUAUGUUUAGAGGUGGAGAUAUUAGGGUAAAUCAGUAUAUUGCUCCUGUCAUCAAAGUUUUUGUUCAUUUGUGUGCCACAUCGAAUAGCAGCACUUCUCAAAGUUUGUCAACUGGAAAAAAGUGUUUAAAACUGUUUUUUUCUUAAGCAGAUUUGGUGAUGUCAUCAAUAUCUAUGAUAUCGAUUGGUAAAAGGUCUUUCUUUGUUGAGGAUUUGAGCUCUCUUUUUAAGAGUUUAUUUUAUUUUAAAGGAACAUAUGCUUUGAAUAACAAUUCUCUGGGCAUGUUUAACUAACCUAGGUGGGAAAACCAUGGUGCUGUUUAAUUGUAAAUAGAUUGAUAUAAGAUUGGACCAGUACUUGAUGUGUAUAAUUUUAGUAUGUAGGGUUUAUGUGCUUUUUUUAAAAAAAAAAAAAAGGUUCAAUUUU